AUGAGCCUUCUGCUGGAUGCCUUCCAGAAAGAGACACUCCACUGUGUAAUGAGAGCUGUGCCCCAGGCCACCCUGCAGGAUCCAGAGAAGAGGCAGAGCCAGGGAGAGGGCAAUGGAGACUGCCACAUAAUCUAUGACAGAUGUGGUGACAGGGGCUGUCAUGGAGGCUGUGACAGAGACUGCGGUGUGGACUGUGAUACACACCGUGACAAGGUCUGUGAUACAGACUGUGACAGGGACUAUGACAGAGGCCGUGAUAGAGACUGUGACAGGGGCUGUGACAGAGACUCUAACAGACGCUGUGAUAGAGACUGUGACAGAGACUGUGAUAGAGGCUGUGAUAGAUACUGUGACAGGCUAGGCUGUGAUAGAGACUGUGAUAGAGACUGUGACAGAGACUGUGACAGAGGCUGUGAUAGAGGCUGUGACAGAGGCUGUGACAGAGGCUGUGACAGAGACUGUGAUAGAGGCUGUGACAGAGGCUGUGACAGAGACUGUGAUAGAGGCUGUGACAGAGGCUGUGACAGAGGCUGUGACAGAGGCUGUGGUAGAGGCUGUGACAGAGACUGUGACAGAGGCUGUGACAGAGGCUGUGAUAGAUACUGUGACAGAGGCUGUGAUAGAGACUGUAAUGCAGACUGUGAUAGAGGCUGUGAUAGAGGCUGUGAUAGAGACUGUGAUAGAGGCUGUGACAGAGGCUGUGAUAGAGGCUGUGAGAGAGGCUGUGACAGAGGCUGUGAUAGAGACUGUGAUAGAGGCUGUGACAGAGGCUGUGAUAGAGACUGUGACAGGGGCUGUGACAGAGGCUGUGAUAGAGACUGUGAUAGAGGCUGUGACAGAUGCUGUGACAGAGGCUGUGAUAGAGGCUGUGAUAGAGGCUGUGACAGAGGCUGUGACAGAGACUGUGAUAGAGGCUGUGGUAGAGGCUGUGGUAGAGGCUGUGACAGAGGCUGUGACAGAGACUGUGACAGAGGCUGUGACAGAGGCUGUGAUAGAUACUGUGACAGAGGCUGUGAUAGAGACUGUAAUACAGACUGUGAUAGAGGCUGUGAUAGAGGCUGUGAUAGAGACUGUGAUAGAGGCUGUGAUACAGACUGUGACAGAGGCUGUGAUAGAGGCUGUGACAGAGACUGUGACAGAGGCCGUGACAGAGGCUGUGAUAGAGGCUGUGACAGAGACUGUGAUAGAGGCUGUGACAGAGGCUGUGACAGAGGUUGUGAUAGAGGCUGUGACAGAGGCUGUGACAGAGGCUGUGAUAGAGGCUGUGACAGAGGCUGUGACAGAGGCUGUGACAGAGACUGUGAUAGAGGCUGUGACAGAGGCUGUGAUAGAGGCUGUGACAGAGGCUGUGACAGAGGCUGUGACAGAGGCUGUGAUAGAGACUGUGACAGGGGCUGCGACAGAGGCUGUGAUAGAGGCUGCGACAGAGGCCGUGAUAGAGGCUGUGAUAGAGGCUGUGACAGAGGCUGUGAUAGAGGCUGUGACAGAGGCUGUGACAGAGGCUGUGAUAGAGGCUGUGACAGAGGCUGUGAUAGAGGCUGUGACAGAGGCUGUGACAGAGACUGUGACAGGGACUGUGACAGAGGCUGUGAGAGAGGCUGUGACAGAGGCUGUGACAGAGGCUGUGAUAGAGACUGUGACAGGGGCUGUGACAGAGGCUGUGACAGAGGCUGUGACAGAGGCUGUGAUAGAGGCUGUGACAGAGGCUGUGACAGAGACUGCAACAGAGACUGUGAGAGAGGCUGUGACAGAGGCUGUGAUAGAGGCUGUGACAGGGGCUGUGACAGAGACUGUGAUAGAGGCUGUGACAGGGGCUGUGAUAGAGGCUGUGACAGAGGCUGUGACAAGGGCUGUGACAAGGGCUGUGACAGAGACUCUGACAGCGACUGUAACAGGAAUUGUGACAGGGGCUGUGACAGAGGCUGUGUUAGAGGCUGGGACAGAGACUCUGACAGGGACAGGGACAGGCACUGCGAUGGGGACUGGGACAGAAAUGUGACUAAAUCUGGAACCACAAUCAGAGUUGGGACAACAGUUCCUGGAGCCCGGGCCCACACUCCCACGGUCGACAGAGCAGUUGGCGGUGACAGCAGCAACACAGCAAACACAGAGGCCCAGCCAGGCCCAGGCAUUUGUGGGGACGCCAGCAGGCUGAAGCUGCCGCGGGAAGACAGCGAGAGGGAGACAUGAUCUGUUCUUGGCAGAUGCUGGUGGCCCCAGAAGCUCGAGCACAGGUGCACUGUCUAGGAAGGGAGCUUGCAGGUGGGAACCCAGCAGGGCCCUGGGUGUCCUUGGGCACUGACAGGGUCCCAACUGUGAGCACCAUCUGCUCCUGUGAAGGGUGUCUGACAGUAGCCGCAGCCCUGGACCUGGAAGGUGAGUACCUCUGAGACCCAAAGUCAGGCUCCCAUUCCCAUCCUCCCUGCCUGUAGGGAGUCCACGGAAAGUCACUUUAACCCUGGAAAUAGAAAGCACCAACAUAUGUACCACUUUGUAAUUUACCAAGUGUUUUCCCACAUA